CAGUCACACAAGAAGGGAGGAGAGAAAAGCCAUGGCCGGUGAGUCUUUUACUGUUCCAAGAACAGGUCCCUGGGAAGAAAGAGUUUUGGAAGGGGCUGGCUCUUCUGGAAGCCAUAAUUAGCAUCUGUGGAAGUUUACUUGAGUAGAAGCAAGGAAAAGGGGGGAGAGGGAGGAGAGAAGGAACUAGAAGAUUCUUGCAGACUUUAGAAAGGAAAGGCAAGCCCAGAAAGGAACUGAGGCUUUAGGGGAAGCCUGAUGUCAUUUUGCAAUCUUAAUUAAACUCUUACUUACAUGUUGAAAGUCUGACAGAGGGUACAGAAUUGGCACAGGAGGAGUACUAGCAGCAGUGGUUCCUAAAUGAAAUGGGCUAUUUCUGCUUCAUUACUUUAUUAACCAGAGUUAAAUAAACAUGCGACAUAAGAGGAUGAUCUCUGCUUUCCAGGGACUGAUGUGGAAAUGGUAAACUCAGUCUUCAGGUCACUCCAUGCACAUGUAUGGAGACUAUUGAGGGAAACAAGUAGGACAGCAAUACAACAAGGUCCUGAAGGAGAAGAGAAAGCUGUUUAUCCGUUCCAUGGGUGAAGGUACAAUAAAUGGCUUACUGGAUGAAUUAUUACAGACAAGGGUGCUGAACAAGGAAGAGAUGGAGAAAGUAAAACGUGAAAAUGCUACAGUUAUGGAUAAGACCCGAGCUUUGAUUGACUCCGUUAUUCCGAAAGGGGCACAGGCAUGCCAAAUUUGCAUCACAUACAUUUGUGAAGAAGACAGUUACCUGGCAGGGACGCUGGGACUCUCAGCAGAUCAAACAUCUGGAAAUUACCUUAAUAUGCAAGACUCUCAAGGAGUACUUUCUUCCUUUCCAGCUCCUCAGGCAGUGCAGGACAACCCAGCUAUGCCCACAUCCUCAGGCUCAGAAGGGAAUGUCAAGCUUUGCUCCCUAGAAGAAGCUCAAAGGAUAUGGAAACAAAAGUCGGCAGAGAUUUAUCCAAUAAUGGACAAGUCAAGCCGCACACGUCUUGCUCUCAUUAUCUGCAAUGAAGAAUUUGACAGUAUUCCUAGAAGAACUGGAGCUGAGGUUGACAUCACAGGCAUGACAAUGCUGCUACAAAAUCUGGGGUACAGCGUAGAUGUGAAAAAAAAUCUCACUGCUUCGGACAUGACUACAGAGCUGGAGGCAUUUGCACACCGCCCAGAGCACAAGACCUCUGACAGCACGUUCCUGGUGUUCAUGUCUCAUGGUAUUCGGGAAGGCAUUUGUGGGAAGAAACACUCUGAGCAAGUCCCAGAUAUACUACAACUCAAUGCAAUCUUUAACAUGUUGAAUACCAAGAACUGCCCAAGUUUGAAGGACAAACCGAAGGUGAUCAUCAUCCAGGCCUGCCGUGGUGACAGCCCUGGUGUGGUGUGGUUUAAAGAUUCAGUAGGAGUUUCUGGAAACCUAUCUUUACCAACUACAGAAGAGUUUGAGGAUGAUGCUAUUAAGAAAGCCCACAUAGAGAAGGAUUUUAUCGCUUUCUGCUCUUCCACACCAGAUAAUGUUUCUUGGAGACAUCCCACAAUGGGCUCUGUUUUUAUUGGAAGACUCAUUGAACAUAUGCAAGAAUAUGCCUGUUCCUGUGAUGUGGAGGAAAUUUUCCGCAAGGUUCGAUUUUCAUUUGAGCAGCCAGAUGGUAGAGCGCAGAUGCCCACCACUGAAAGAGUGACUUUGACAAGAUGUUUCUACCUCUUCCCAGGACAUUAAAAUAAGGAAACUGUAUGAAUGUCUGUGGGCAGGUACAUGUGUAUGGUCGGGAGUGUGGGAAGGUUGAGGAAAGGGUACUGAAAGUCCAUUUGAGUCAAGAACUCUAGGUUUACAGGCUGAGAAUCCUUAAUCCAAAAAUUUGAAUUUUGAAAUGCUCUAAAAUCCAACACUGUGUGAGCGCCCACAUGAUAUUCAAAGGAAAUGUUUAUUGAAACAUUUCAAAUUAUAGGUUUUUGGAUUAGGGAUGCUAAACCAGUAAGUAUACAGCUGAAUUCCAAUAUACAAAAAUAUCUGAAAUUUGAAAUACUUCUGGUAGCAUGCAUUUUGGAUAAGGGAUAAUCAAGCCAUAUACAGAAAAUACUGAAGUAAUGCCUUUCUUCUGGUCAGUGCAGAGCACGUUGCUCUUCUCCCAAAGUUUUUCAUUUAGACCCCUUUUGAGAUUCAUCUGAUAUUGGCCUAGAAGUGGCCGUAAGACUACAAACCCUCACUUUUGGAUGUUUCUCUCCUUCACCUCAGCAGGGUAUAUUUAAACAUAGCAUGUGGUCUUUCCUUUUAAAAUUGUGUAUGUUCCCAUUGGUGGUAUAACUUUAUAACUUGCAUGUCUUUAACAAAAUUCUUUCCUAUGUUUUUUUUUUUAAUUAUUUCUUUUUCUCAUAGGAAGUGAAGAGAUCCUUCUGUAAAGGUUUUUGGAAUUAUGUCUGCUGAAUAAUAAACUUUUUUGAAAUAAUAAAUCUGGUAGAAAAAUGAAAA